GGGCAGAGCUCGGCCGCUGCGGAGGACAAGGAACUCUCCCUCUCCCACUAGUCUGACUUCUUCCAAAAUGAGCGGCCUGGAUGGGGGCAACAAGCUCCCUCUCGCCCAAACCGGCGGCCUGGCUGCUCCCGACCAUGCCUCAGGAGAUCCGGACCGAGACCAGUGCCAAGGGCUCCGUGAAGAAACCGAGGCGACACAGGUGAUGGCGAACACAGGUGGGGGCAGCCUGGAGACCGUUGCGGAGGGGGGUGCAUCCCAGGAUCCUGUCGACUGUGGCCCCGCGCUCCGCGUCCCAGUUGCCGGGAGUCGCGGCGGUGCAGCGACCAAAGCCGGGCAGGAGGAUGCUCCACCUUCUACGAAAGGUCUGGAAGCAGCCUCUGCCGCCGAGGCUGCUGACAGCAGCCAGAAAAAUGGCUGUCAGCUUGGAGAGCCCCGUGGCCCUGCUGGGCAGAAGGCUCUAGAAGCCUGUGGCGCAGGGGGCUUGGGGUCUCAGAUGAUACCGGGGAAGAAGGCCAAGGAAGUGACGACUAAAAAACGCGCCAUCUCGGCAGCAGUGGAAAAGGAGGGAGAAGCAGGGGCGGCGAUGGAGGAAAAGAAGGUAGUGCAGAAGGAAAAAAAGGUGGCAGGAGGGGUGAAAGAGGAGACACGGCCCAGGGCCCCGAAGAUCAAUAACUGCAUGGACUCACUGGAGGCCAUCGAUCAAGAGUUGUCAAACGUAAAUGCCCAGGCUGACAGGGCCUUCCUUCAGCUUGAGCGCAAGUUUGGCCGCAUGCGAAGGCUCCACAUGCAGCGCAGAAGUUUCAUUAUCCAGAAUAUCCCAGGUUUCUGGGUUACUGCCUUUCGAAACCACCCCCAGCUGUCACCUAUGAUCAGUGGCCAAGAUGAAGACAUGCUGAGGUACAUGAUCAAUUUGGAGGUGGAGGAGCUUAAACACCCCAGAGCAGGCUGCAAAUUCAAGUUCAUCUUUCAGGGCAACCCCUACUUCCGAAAUGAGGGGCUUGUCAAGGAAUAUGAACGCAGAUCCUCUGGCCGGGUGGUGUCUCUUUCCACUCCAAUCCGCUGGCACCGAGGCCAAGACCCCCAGGCUCAUAUCCACAGAAACCGGGAAGGGAACACUAUCCCUAGUUUCUUCAACUGGUUUUCAGACCACAGCCUUCUAGAAUUCGACAGAAUUGCAGAGAUUAUCAAAGGAGAACUGUGGCCCAAUCCCCUACAAUACUACCUGAUGGGUGAAGGGCCCCGUAGAGGAAUUCGAGGCCCACCAAGGCAGCCAGUGGAGAGCGCCAGAUCCUUCAGGUUCCAGUCUGGCUAAUCUCUGUCCUGUGAGAAGCUUCUGCACAAGUUUCCUUACCACCUCCUCUUGGACCUAUGCUUGGCCAACAGCAUGCAGUCUUCCAUCUGCUUUCUCUUCAUACUGUGGAUUAUCUUUUCCUUUGGUUCUAAAUCUUCAGUAAUCGGUUGCAAGAUUGUUGGCUUACCUGCCUGUGCCAUUCUUCCUCUGGGCCUUCAUGCUUUUCUGCAUUGUGUUAACAUGUUUCAAGUGCAUGGCCUUCUACGGCUUCUAUGCCAAGCGUAUGAUACUAUAGAUAUAGUGUACCAUACUGCCUUUCUUUGCAUGGCUUGGACCCUAUCUGUGACCAUGCUCUUCUCCCAAUUUAAGUGGUUCUGUACCACAAAGAAUCUUGAUACAUUUUCACAAAUAACUGAUUGGGCUUCAUACUUUAUGCUGGCUGUGUCCUGAUACCCAUGUACUUAUGGUAAGCUAUUUGGGUAUUACCACUGCAAGACAAAACUGAUAUCUUAACCCGGCCAUCAACCCAAAUUGGACAUUCCAGACUACCACCAACUGGAUCCCAGCUGCCUUCCUGGGCUUGUGCCAUCCACCCUACUGGUUAUCUGAUAGAACAAGCUGGUGGCUGAUGGGUGACUGCUAGGCGUGACUGAGGUAAUAGAUGAAAAGUGUUCUAUGUUAUCACAUUGGUUUUCCUGUACCUUUGGUUACUCUACGUCAUGACCAGCUGCUGGUGAGUAUGAAGCCUGUGCUAUAGCCCACCCCUACUCACUCUCACCUUCUGGUUGAACUUUGCUUAGGCCACCAUUGUCUGCCUCAUCAGGAACUAUCUGUAGACGUAGCUCCCAGGGAGCUCACAGCAACACCCCCUACCACCAGGAUGGGCAGUAAUAUGUGACAGAGCCCAAAGCAAGGCUGGAACGCAGUCCCUUCCAGCUUAGUCUUUCUGACUCCUAGCCAACAAACCAUCCUUAAUGUGAGCAACUUCUUUAGGCAUUUCCUCUUUUCCCCGCCUGCACCCACUCUGAACAUGACAAAAGUUGCCAGAGUUGGGGCAUUGAGGAAGAGAUAUUUCUGGAAUGUGAGACUUGUUAUGCCUCUGUCUCUUUCUCUCCCUCCUCCUCCCCUCUCCCUCCCCCUCUCCCUCCCAUCCCUUUUCUUCCCUUUCACUCUGAAGCAGUUUUAGCUUAUUAACAGAAAACAAAACUGGCAAAGCAGGCUUUUUGUUUAAUUUGCUCUUUCCCUGAUUGUGUUCAGAGAGAAAGGUUAUGAUUAAAUGGGCUCCAGAUCUCUUAUUGCCCUUAUUCCUCCACCCCACUUCUUUUAGCAAGGUCUGAAAGUUUCAAAGGGAGACCUAUAGGUUAAUUGUUUAGUUAUAGGCAGUGUUAAAUUAGGCAGAUUUUGACAUAUUUAUCUUUUUACCCCAUCCAUUCUACCAAAACCUGUGUAUUUCUUGAGUUUUUAGUUUGAGAAGCUGGAAAGAGAGAGAAGGGCCUCACAGUGAUGGGUUCAGGACGGGUCAAAGGCAAAGGCCUUUGUGAUGUGAGCAAAGGCAACCAAAACUUAGCCUCACUCCACUUUUCUAAAGAUGGAAAUUCUUUUUUGGGCCUUGGACUGCUUCUAGGGUAGCAUUUUGUAGGUCACUCUUCUCCUUUGUACUAUUUUGUUUCUGCCCUGAUGUCCCUUGGGUCUCCAUCCUACUGCCUGGCUUUCUUGGCCCUCAUUUCUCAGCUUCUGCAUUUCCUUCCCUGCUCCUAACAAAUGAAGAAGCAGGCUGCAGCCUGCAUUGUGGAAGAUCUCCAGCCUCCUUGUAGGGGAUAAGGGGAUGUGCAGCAUCUGUGUGGAUUUUCACGGACAAGUUCCAGUAGGUGGGACAGUGAUGCCGUCAAGGCUUAGUUAUGAUCAUGUGUGGUGAUAAAGACCAUCCACCAUCACCCUUUUCCCCUUUGGUUUUGAAGGCCUUGCCCUAAGCUACCUGAGGGUUUAGGAGGUCUGAACACACACAGUGGAGAGGUUAAUCUAGGUUGGGAAACUGAGUAAAAGUCCAGAGCAGGAAUGAGCCUGCUGUGGCGUGGGUUUGGAAAGGCUCACAGGAAAGAACCUGCAGGAUCAGGGGUGGGAGGGGAGGCCCCUGAGGUGCUCUCCAGGGAAGAGGGGCUGGGGUUUAAAUAGCAUGCUUGGAGGAAGAUUUUCCUUCAAUUUUUCCUAAGUCCUUGAAUUCACCAGUAGAUUUUUGUAAACAAAAUGUAAGUCGAUGUUUUCUCUCAAUUAUCCUAGGAGUGACCUUUAUAUGUGUGGAAGAUUAAUGGUAUAUGCUCCUUAUGUCACUGUUUUUGAGUAAAAUCCAUUUCCUUUCUCUGUUUCAGCCUAUGACAAAAUUGAUGUUUACAGGCCUGCUUUUUGCUUAUAAUUGACAACAUGUGCAAAAAUACCAAAUUUGUGUCCUGUGCAGUAUGAAGAAUUCAGUGAAUAUUCAUUAAUGUAUUAGCUUGUUUUGCUCUCUGUUCAUAUAUGGCUCUAUUCUUAGAAAUAUAAUUUGAAUGUGAUCUUUCAAUAGUCUGAAUAUUUUACAAAUUAUAGCUAUGUCUUGUGAAAAUAACCUCAAAAAGAAAAAUACGACUCUGUUGUCUUACUUGAUAUUUCUUGCCCUAGUAAUGUACUUGACAUUUAUGUUCCUAAGCAGUGUAAGUACCAGUAGAAUUUCUCUGUCAAACUCAAUGAUCAUUUAGUACUUUUGUCUUCUCCCAUGUGCUUGAAGGAAAAAUAAAGUGUCACUACCGUAUUUCUUGUUUUCAUCAAAAAAUAAAAAUAAUUUAAAAAA